ACUGCUCCCGCUCCAUUGUCUGGGAAUUGCAGCCGCGGGGCGGGCGGCGGCGGCGGCGGCGGCGGCCGGGACCCAGCGGGCCAGGUGGGGACGGCGCGGAGCGGGUGCGGGAGAUGCCGUGCGGGACUGGGGCCACCUGAGCCGCCCGCCUCGUCCCCGCCUUCUGUGGGAAGGAUGUGCGCGCGGAUGGCCGGUCGCACAACAGCGGCCCCUCGGGGGCCCUACGGCCCCUGGCUCUGCCUCCUGGUGGCCCUCGCCCUGGACGUCGUGAGAGGUCAGCGGGAGGGGAGGGCCGGGGCGAGGGGCGGCCGGGCCCGGCCGAGUGGGAGCGAGUGAUGCCCGGGAGCCACCAACCUUUGGGUUCUCGGACUGAACCCUGAGCGGGGUCGCCCCGCAGCGCCCUGAAGGUCGGAGAGUUCUUGCCCUCGGGAACCUGCCCCCAGCCACUCGCCCCUAAGGCUUCCUUCACCUUGCACGACCCGGCAACUCCUUCCUGACCCGGGGCAGCCCGGCGCAGGGGCUUCCCCGUCCCGCACCUUCUGCGAGGGACCCCUCAGCCCGGGCAUCGAACCCGGCGGCCCCGGUCCCGGGCGCACUAGCGUCAUCCCCACUCCCUCACUGUGGUCUGUAGCGCUGCACCCUCCUAGCCUCCUUCCGCCGCCACCAACCCACCCCCCUCGGGAGUGGAAAGCAGCCCCUUUGCCUGGGACCUGCAACAGACGCAAGCCCUCCCUCCCCCUUCCCCCAGGGCUCCCUGACCUUGGCGUCUCCAGGGAUGGCCGCAUCCUUGCCUUCCAGAACCUUUGAGAGGAUUCCUGUCACUGCGGGAAAGGGCAGCAACUUCCCUGUGCUUCGGGGUGGGGGUCGGACUCCCUUGGCCUGGGCUAGCUGGGCUGUGGCUGCAAGGCAAAGGAUGCCACAGAAGACAGAGGGACAGUGAAACAUUCUCUGCCCUCCCCACCGAGAGAGCCGAGCGCUGGGUGAUGGGAGUCCGUGGGAGUCAGGCUAAGAGCAUCUUGUAAUUAUGGAGGCAAUGGAGUAGGAGGCGAACCUGAAGCCAGUGGCUGCCCCCAGAGAGCAGUGGUCACUUGUUACGCUUGGGGCAGGGGGCAGGGAGAGCCUGUCAGUCAUAUGCUCCUUGGUGGGGAGGGCCAGGAAGGAGGUUGAAACCAAUUCCCCCACCCCCACCCACAGUCCAGCUGUGGGGCUGAGAGGGAGCUAGCUGUGGGGUUGCUUUCAGCCACCUGCUCCCCAUCCCGAGGGACGCCAUGGGAGUCCUAAUAGAGAGAGGAGGAAAACCUUGUCAAAUCCAUUAUGCAGCAGCAAUAAUGCCUGCUCCCUCCAGACAGCACUCCACAGUUUACACAGCCCUGUCCUGUCCACAGUGCCACCUAAUGCUCCUGCCCCUUUUACAAGUGAGGAAACAGGCUUCAAAAUGUUAAUGCCUGACCCAAGUUUCAUCAAUUUAAAUUCAGGUCUCCAGGCUCCCAGGAAAUCCUCUCUAGGGAGCGCUUCCUAGUUUGGGGGAAUUCCAGGAUGAGCAAGACAGGGUCCCUUGUUUAUAGGAAGAUUACUAAUUCAGAGGAGGCACCCAGGGUUGCAAAAGACAGGAGACUGGUGGGAAGGUGAGUAACCAAGGAGGGCUUCCUUCAGAAGGAGGCAGUAUUCACUCAUGGCCCUGAAUGAGGAGGGAGGUGCCACCGGGCAGAGCAGAGGAGAGGAGGUGCGCUCCAGGGCAUGAAGCCUGCAGGGUGCACCGUGGCAGUGGAGAGUGGAGAGAGAAGUGGCAGGUGGAGACGCCGGAUGGUCUAGUGGCUAAUACCUGGGAUCAACCCCCAGCUCCUUCACUCUCCAGCUGUGGAACCACAGGCAAAUACCUUAACCUCUCGGCCUCAUUUUCUACAUCCACAAAAUGGGAUUCAUCAUAAUAGAACCUGGUUCACAGAAUUAUUACAAAGACUCAAAGAGUUCAUAUACAUACAGUAUUUAAAUUCUCACCUGCAUAUAGCAUUCACAAAAUGCUAAUUAUUAUUAUUAGUGCUCAUAGUUAGAGCAAACCAAUAUGGCUUAGUGCUCCUUUGUCCUUCUGAUGAUUGACUAUUUUGACUGUCUUCCCCAGGCUCCUGGUCCCCACCCCACCCCCAGGGCAAGCAAGUGCCUUCACAGACCUCUUCAGCACCUUCCGCGCCCGCCCAUCCCACACUUGCACUCGAUACCAGUCGGUUCAGGGAAGAAGGGAGCAAGCUUGGAAAGAUGGUGCAGGUUGCCAUGGCAAUGAUGGGGGAGGAGGGGUGGAUGCCCAGCAGAGCCUGGCCAAGGAUUCAGGGCAGAGAAAGCUCACUUCAUUACCAUAUUUUACUACACUGGCCCAGUCUGCCGACGGUUGCACCCCAGAAGUGCCUUGGUAUCAGAGGCGAGUAGAUGGAGGGCAGGAGUUGGGGAAAAGGAGACAUUGAGAAGGCUGUUGGCGAGAAGAAGGCCAAGGUCUGUGGAAAGUAGAAGGAAUAGCUGGGAAGCAUCCAGUCCUGGACUCAGAUUCGAAUCCUGGCUUUGCUACAUACUACCUGUGUGAGGCUCUUUAAGCCUCAGUGACCUCAUCUGUGAAAUGGUGGUGAGAGGGGAAGGGACAUUUACAGCCCUUUUCUCCCUCCCUUGCCCACAACUACUGUGCCCCAGCAUGGCACCCGGGUCAGCCCCUGCCAGCUCUGGAGCUGUCAUCAUCUCUCCCUCUUAUGCCUCUUCAGUGGACUGUGGCCAGGCUCCCCUGGACCCUGUCUACCUGCCGGCAGCCCUGGAGCUCCUAGACGCCCCUGAACACUUCCGUGUGCAGCAGGUGGGCCACUACCCACCUGCCAACUCCUCUCUGAGCUCCCGAUCUGAGACCUUUCUGCUCCUACAGCCCUGGCCCAGGGCCCAGCCACUUCUCCGGGCCUCCUACCCACCUUUUGCCACUCAGCAGGUGGUCCCCCCUCGAGUCACUGAGCCCCACCAACGGCCAGUCCCAUGGGACGUGCGGGCCGUUUCAGUGGAAGCGGCUGUGACUCCAGCAGAGCCCUACGCCCGGGUUCUCUUCCACCUCAAAGGGCAGGAUUGGCCACCAGGGUCUGGCAGCCUGCCCUGUGCCCGGCUCCAUGCCACACACCCUGCCGGCACUGCUCACCAAGCCUGCCGCUUCCAGCCAUCCCUGGGCGCCUGCGUGGUGGAGCUGGAGCUUCCCUCGCACUGGUUCUCACAGGCCUCCACCACACGGGCCGAGCUGGCCUACACGCUUGAGCCUGCAGCUGAGGGCCCUGGGGGCUGUGGCUCCGGCGAGGAGAACGACCCUGGGGAGCAGGCCCUCCCAGUGGGGGGUGUGGAGCUGCGCCCAGCAGACCCCCCGCAGUACCAGGAGGUACCUCUGGACGAGGCUGUGACUCUGCGGGUGCCUGACAUGCCAGUGCGGCCCGGCCAGCUCUUUAGUGCUACCCUCCUGCUUCGGCACAACUUCACAGCCAGCCUCCUGACCCUGCGGAUCAAGGUGAAGAAGGGGCUGCAUGUGACAGCCGCCCGCCCAGCCCAGCCCACACUCUGGACUGCCAAGCUGGACCGCUUCAAGGGCUCCAGGCACCACACCACCCUCAUCACCUGCCACCGUGCUGGGCUCACAGAGCCAGAUUCCAGCAGUCCCCUUGAACUGUCUGAGUUCCUAUGGGUGGACUUUGUGGUGGAGAAUAGCACUGGUGGGGGCGUAGCGGUCACUCGCCCCGUCACGUGGCAGCUGGAGUACCCAGGCCAGGCCCCUGAAGCAGAGAAGGACAAAAUGGUGUGGGAAAUCCUGGUGUCUGAGCGGGACAUCAGAGCCCUUAUCCCACUGGCCAAGGCUGAGGAGCUGGUGAAUACAGCACCACUGACUGGAGUGCCCCAGCAUGUCCCCGUGCGCCUUGUCACUGUGGACGGCGGGGGGGCCUUGGUGGAGGUGACAGAGCAUGUCGGCUGCGAGUCUGCCAACACACAGGUCCUGCAGGUGUCUGAGGCCUGUGAUGCCGUGUUCGUGGCUGGCAAGGAGAGCCGGGGCGCCCGGGGGGUGCGAGUGGACUUCUGGUGGCGCCGGCUCCGCGCCUCGCUGCGGCUGACCGUGUGGGCCCCCCUGCUACCGCUGCGUAUCGAGCUCACCGACACCACCCUCGAGCAGGUCCGCGGCUGGAGGGUACCUGGCCCUGCUGAAGGGCCUGCGGAACCCGCUGCAGAGGCGUCGGAUGAGGCCGAGCGGCGCGCCCGUGGCUGCCACCUGCAGUACCAGCGGGCCGGUGUGCGCUUCCUCGCCCCCUUCGCGGCCCACCCGCUGGACGGCGGCCGCCGCCUCACGCACCUGCUUGGCCCCGACUGGCUGCUAGACGUGUCCCACCUCGUGGCGCCACACGCCCGCGUGCUGGACUCGCGUGUAGCCUCUCUGGAGGGUGGCCGUGUCGUGGUGGGCCGGGAGCCCGGUGUCACCUCCAUUGAGGUGCGUUCCCCACUGUCUGACUCCAUCCUGGGGGAGCAGGCGCUGGCUGUGACGGACGACAAGGUCUCAGUGCUGGAGCUGAGGGUGCAGCCAGUGAUGGGCAUCUCGCUGACCUUGAGCCGGGGCACUGCCCACCCCGGGGAGGUCACAGCUACGUGCUGGGCACAGUCAGCCCUUCCCGCCCCAAAGCAGGAGGUGGCCCUCUCCCUAUGGCUGUCCUUCUCUGAUCACACUGUGGCCCCAGCUGAGCUCUACGACCGCCGUGACCUGGGACUGUCCGUCUCAGCCGAGGAGCCUGGUGCCAUCCUGCCAGCUGAGGAGCAGGGUGCCCAGCUCGGGGUGGUGGUGAGUGGGGCAGGCGCCGAGGGGCUGCCGCUGCAUGUGGCUCUGCACCCGCCCGAGCCCUGCCGCCGGGGCCGCCACCGUGUGCCUCUGGCCUCUGGCACCGCCUGGCUGGGGCUGCCCCCUGCCUCCACUCCAGCCCCUGCUCUCCCAUCCAGCCCUGCUUGGAGCCCACCAGCCACAGAAGCCACCAUGGGUGGUAAACGGCAGGUGGCAGGCAGUGUCGGGGGCAACACAGGUGUGAGGGGCAAGUUUGAGCGGGCAGAGGAGGAGGCCAGGAAGGAGGAGACCGAAGCCAGGGAGGAGGAGGAGGAAGAGGAGGAGGAGAUGGUCCCUGCCCCUCAGCAUGUCACUGAGCUAGAGCUGGGCAUGUACGCCCUGCUGGGAGUCUUCUGCGUGGCCAUCUUCAUCUUCUUGGUCAAUGGUGUGGUCUUCGUCCUGCGCUAUCAGCGCAAAGAACCUCCCGACAGUGCCACUGACCCCACCUCCCCCCAGCCCCACAACUGGGUCUGGCUGGGCACUGACCAGGAGGAACUGAGCCGCCAGCUGGACCGGCAGUCCCCUGGCCCGCCCAAGGGGGAGGGGAGCUGCCCCUGUGAGAGUGGGGGAGGAGGGGAGGCCCCUACCCUGGCCCCUGGCCCUCCUGGGGGCACCACCAGCUCCUCAAGCACCCUGGCCCGAAAGGAGGCUGGGGGGCGGCGGAAGCGAGUAGAGUUUGUGACAUUUGCGCCAGCCCCUCCAGCCCAGUCACCUGAGGAGCCUGUAGGGGCCCCUGCUGUGCAGUCCAUCCUUGUGGCAGGCGAGGAGGACAUCCGCUGGGUGUGUGAGGACAUGGGGCUGAAGGACCCUGAGGAGCUUCGCAACUACAUGGAGAGGAUCCGGGGCAGCUCCUGACCCUCCACAGCCACCUGGUCAGCCACCAGCUGGGGCAACGAGGGUGGAGGUCCCACUGAGCCUCUCGCCUGCCCCCGCCACUCGUCUGGUGCUUGUUGAUCCAAGUCCCCUGCCUGGUCCCCCACAAGGACUCCCAUCCAGGCCCCCUCUGCCCUGCCCCUUGUCAUGGACCAUGGUCGUGAGGAAGGGCUCAUGCCCCUUAUUUAUGGGAACCAUUUCAUUCUAACAGAAUAAACCGAGAAGGAAACCAGA